GCCUCGGAAGCCCCUGAGAGCCGGCAGAUGGGGGGCUUUUAGCCACGGUCUCUGGUCUGAUGAAGCAGAAAAGAAGAUGAGGAUCAGGGGGUCCUCGGGAACGCUGUCACGAAUCAAUAUGUUAAGGAUACCUGUAAGAAAGGCCUUAGUAGGCCUUUCUAAGUCUCCUAAAGGAUGUGUUCGAACAACUGCCACAGCAGCAAGCAACUUGAUUGAAGUAUUUGUUGAUGGUCAGUCUGUCAUGGUGGAACCGGGAACGACCGUCCUCCAAGCUUGUGAGAAGGUUGGCAUGCAGAUCCCUCGAUUCUGUUAUCAUGAAAGGUUGUCUGUUGCUGGAAACUGCAGGAUGUGCCUUGUUGAAAUUGAGAAAGCCCCUAAGGUUGUAGCUGCUUGUGCCAUGCCAGUAAUGAAGGGUUGGAAUAUCCUAACAAACUCAGAAAAAUCCAAAAAAGCCAGGGAAGGUGUGAUGGAGUUCUUAUUAGCAAAUCACCCAUUGGACUGUCCUAUUUGUGACCAGGGAGGUGAAUGUGAUCUGCAGGACCAGUCCAUGAUGUUUGGAAAUGAUAGGAGCCGAUUUUUAGAGGGGAAGCGUGCUGUGGAAGACAAGAACAUUGGGCCAUUGGUAAAGACCAUCAUGACAAGAUGUAUACAGUGUACUCGCUGCAUCAGGUUUGCAAGUGAGAUUGCAGGAGUAGAUGAUUUGGGAACAACAGGCAGAGGAAAUGAUAUGCAAGUUGGCACAUACAUUGAAAAGAUGUUCAUGUCUGAACUGUCUGGGAAUAUCAUUGAUAUCUGCCCUGUAGGUGCCCUAACCUCUAAGCCCUAUGCCUUUACUGCCCGGCCUUGGGAAACAAGAAAGACAGAAUCCAUUGAUGUAAUGGAUGCGGUUGGAAGUAAUAUUGUGGUUAGCACAAGAACUGGAGAAGUGAUGAGGAUUUUGCCACGUAUGCAUGAGGACAUCAAUGAAGAGUGGAUCUCUGAUAAAACCAGAUUUGCCUAUGAUGGGCUAAAACGUCAAAGACUUACCGAGCCAAUGGUCAGAAAUGAAAAAGGGCUUUUAACCUAUACUUCUUGGGAGGAUGCGCUCUCUCGCGUAGCUGGAAUGUUGCAGAGUUUUCAAGGCAAAGAUGUGGCAGCAAUUGCAGGUGGCUUGGUGGAUGCUGAAGCCCUGGUAGCUCUCAAAGAUUUGCUUAAUAGAGUGGACUCUGACACCUUAUGCACUGAAGAGGUCUUCCCCACUGCAGGAGCUGGCACAGAUUUGCGUUCCAAUUAUCUUCUUAAUACUACAAUUGCUGGUGUGGAAGAGGCAGAUGUUGUUCUUCUGGUUGGUACAAACCCACGUUUUGAGGCACCACUGUUUAAUGCUAGAAUUCGAAAGAGCUGGCUGCAUAAUGACUUAAAAGUGGCCCUUAUAGGCAGUCCAGUGGACCUCACUUACACAUAUGACCACCUGGGAGACUCCCCCAAAAUUCUUCAAGACAUUGCUUCGGGAAGCCAUCCAUUUAGCCAGGUCCUAAAGGAAGCUAAAAAACCAAUGGUGGUUUUAGGCAGUUCUGCACUCCAAAGAAAUGAUGGAGCAGCAAUUCUUGCAGCUGUUUCUAGCAUUGCACAAAAGAUUCGGAUGACUAGUGGUGUUACUGGUGAUUGGAAAGUUAUGAAUAUCCUUCAUAGGAUUGCAAGUCAAGUAGCUGCUUUGGACCUUGGCUAUAAGCCUGGGGUGGAAGCAAUUCGGAAGAACCCUCCCAAGGUGCUGUUUCUCCUGGGAGCAGAUGGAGGUUGUAUCACACGACAGGAUUUGCCAAAGGAUUGUUUCAUUAUUUAUCAAGGACAUCAUGGUGAUGUUGGGGCUCCCAUAGCUGAUGUUAUUCUCCCAGGAGCUGCUUACACAGAGAAGUCUGCUACAUAUGUCAACACUGAGGGUAGAGCUCAGCAGACUAAGGUAGCAGUGACACCUCCUGGCUUGGCAAGAGAAGACUGGAAAAUUAUAAGAGCACUCUCUGAGAUUGCUGGAAUGACUCUUCCAUAUGAUACUCUGGAUCAAGUAAGGAACAGAUUGGAAGAAGUCUCUCCUAAUCUUGUUCGAUAUGAUGAUAUUGAAGGGGCUAAUUACUUCCAGCAAGCAAAUGAGCUCUCAAAGCUAGUGAACCAGCAGCUUCUUGCUGACCCACUUGUUCCACCUCAGCUAACUAUAAAAGACUUCUACAUGACAGAUUCAAUUAGCAGAGCCUCACAGACAAUGGCCAAAUGUGUCAAAGCUGUCACAGAGGGUGCCCAGGCAGUAGAGGAACCAUCCAUAUGCUGAAGCUUCUACUAGGAUCCCAGUUUUGCCGCAGAUAAUUAAUGGACAACUGUAGUGCAGUGAUCCUUUACAGGUUUAUUUCUUUGUAAAAAAAAAUAAUAAUAAUUUGAAUCAUGUAAUAUUUAAGGUUAUACUAUGCCUAUUUGAAAAUGAUAUUAGUUAUCAACUUUGCAGUUUGAAAAACAUGUAUUGUGUGUAAAGGUUAAAUAACAAAACUAUGCAGAUGCUCUUAAAAGCAUUGAUAACCUUUGUGACGAACAUAAAGAGAUCCUUAAAUUAUGAGUUGUUGGCUUAUCUUCAUAAAUAAUUUGUCUGUAAAAUGGAUGAAAUGAAAAGAGGUUCAAUUAAAACCUACUUUUUUCUAGUGCUAAAGAAAAGAUUUAAGCACCUUGUCAAGCUGGGUAAAUAGGAAAAAUACAUAAUCAUGCUCAGAUAUGUAUCUAGGAUAAUUAUAAUUAAUAAUAAUCAUAGUAACAAUGGCUAAUGAUAAUUUAGCUUUAUUAUAUGUGCUAAGCACUCUGGUUUUACAUGCAUUAUCUUCUUUUGUUCUUGCUACAACCCUGUGAGAUAGUAGUAUUAUCUCAUUUUACUGAUGAAGACUGAAGCCUAGGUAUAUUAAAUAGCUUGCCCAAGGCCACACAGCAAAAGUCACCAACUCAAACCUACUUCUUAUUUACUCCAAAGCCUGUUGUUCUUAACUGCAACAUAUUAUUUCGUCUCAUUAAUGUUGAUUCUAUAGGUUGUUACUUCUAAAAAUUAGUAUUGAGUUUAAUGGUGAACACAUUUUUCUAUUUUCUCUUGAAUCUGCUUCUAUAAUGUCAUGGUGAUUUAUGUGGCUUUUUUUUUUUUAUAAGUUAUACAUGUAUGCAUGUAUACUUAUGAGACCUCCCUUGGAAUGAGGGAGGUCUCAAGAGAUAUAAUUUAGAUUCUCAUUGAUGUUCUGUAUUCAUUAUCCUAACACCAUCUGUAGUGUUAAAUCAACUAAAUUAUUUCAGCAAUAGGAGACAAAACAACCAGCUUUCAUAAUUUUUAAUUGUCAAAACCAAAAGGAAUCAGAAUAAGGAUCACUGAGAAUUUAAAAAAAUAAAAAAGGAAGUAAAAAUUUUACAAUUAGGAGAUAAUUAAAAAUAGAUAAUUUUUUUUUUUAAUCUAAGGUUGGGUGUGGUGGCUUACACCUGUAAUCCCAACACUUGGGGGGCCAAGGUGGGUGGAUCGCUUGAGCCCAGGCAGUUGGAGACCAGUCUGGGCAACAUGGUGAAACCCCAUCUCUACAAAAAAUACAAAAAUUAGCUGGGUGUGGUGGUGUACACCUAUAGUCCCAGCUACUCGGAAGGCUGAGGUGGGAGGAUCACCUGACCCAGGAGGUUGAGGCUGCAGUGAGCCGUGAUUGCGCCACUGCAUUCCAGCCUGGGCAACAGAGCAAGACUUUGUUUCAAACAAACAAACAAAACUAUGUUCACAAUUUAUUUGUUUUGUAAUCCUUAUUCUUUUCUGCUUUCACUAAAGACUCAGCCCAAGUAUAGGAUGCCCUUUUUCCCUUUGUUUUUUUUUUUUUUUUGAGAUGGAGUCUUACUCUGUCACCCAAGGCUGGAAUGCAGUGGCAUGAUCUUGGCUCACUGCAAUCACCACCUCCCUGAUUCAAGCGAUUCUCCUGCCUCAGCCUCCCCGGUAGCUGGGAUUACAAGCGCACGCCACCACACCUGGCUAAUUUUUGUAUUUUUAGUAGAGACAGGGUUUCACCAAUUUGGCCAGGCUGGUCUUGAACUCCUAACCUCAGGUGAUCUACCUGCCUUGGCCUCCCAAAGUGCUGGGAUUACAGGCGUGAGCCACCGCGCCCAGUCUAGGAUGUCGUUUUUCUGAUACAACAAAGGAUAAGGUUUUAGAAUAAUAGUAUGUUACAAUAUCUUUAAAAACAGCAGGUGCAGUGGCUCACACCUGUAAGCCCAGCAUUUUGGGGGUUCAAGGCAGGAAGAUCAGUUGAGGCCAGGAGUUCAAGACCAGCCUGGACUGCAUAGCAAGAUCCUAUUUGUACAAAAAAAUGUAAAACUUAAAAUUGCACAAAAUUUGUCACCUGUACCAGCUUUUAGAACUGUUUAUCUUAUCCUCCUCAGUGAUACAUCAUGAAGUUGUGUGCUUUGCCUAAAAUGCCCAGUUACCUGAAAUUGUAUAAAUUCUUGCCAAAAGUGUUUGAACUUAAUACAAACUUCCCAUCUCUUACCUCUUAGCACUGUGCUCAUCUUGAGGGGACAUAGUCCCAAUUUUGUAUUUUAUAUAAUACUGUUAAUGAAUAUGUGUAGACUUCAUAUGGUUGUGGGUAAGAGAAUACUGCAUUCAGAUAGAAAAGAUGCUAUAUAGCUAAGUUGAUCCAGGAUCCUUGGGCUACCUGCUAGGCAGCUUGUGGUGAACAAUCAUAAUCUCUAAAAAAUACCUUGUCUGGACCGGGCGCGGUGGCUCACACCUGUAAUCCCAGCACUUUGGCAGGCUGAGGCGGGCAGAUCAUUGAGGUCAGGAGUUUGAGACCAGCCUGGCCAACGUGGUGAAACCCUGUCUCUACUAAAAAUACAAAAAUUAGCCAGGCAUGGUGGCACAUGGCUGUAAUCCCAGCUACUGGGGAGGCUGAAGCAGGAAAAUCGCUUGAACUGAGAGUCAAGGCGGAGGUCGCGGUAAGCCGAGAUCACACCAUUGCACUGCAGCCUGGGUGAAGAAACAAGCCUCCCUCUCAAAAAAUAAAUAAAUAAAUAAAUAAUACCUCCUCUGGGAUAAGUAGUGCUCCGUCUGUCUCAUGGGCACAUAUUAGUGUCGUAAUGCCAAAUACUAAGGUUAUUGUAAGCAUAAACAUUGAAGAUAAUUGCUAGAGAAAAAUAGACUGAAAAAGAUGUAAGAAAAAUACACGUAGAUGAGAGUAACCUGUCUGGUGGAAUCAUGACAUUCUAAGCAGUGAAGGAAUCACCAAUGAGAAAAUCUACAAAGGCUCAAGAUCAAGUCUCUUUAGGUGAAUAAGGCAAUCUAGAAAGACCUUGGAAUAAUAAUACCAUUUCCUGAGGACCUUCUAAAUAAGUGCCAUUAAAGCUUUAAAUACAUUAAGACUAUUCUUCACAAAAUCUCUGCUAAUAGUAGGUAUUAAUUGAGACUCAAGAAAUAUCAAAUAACUUAUUUAUGGCUACACAGCUAGAUACUAAUGGCAGGAGUGUUUAAUUAGAAGUACUUUUACUAUCCCAGGUUGCCUCAAAUGAAAACAUUUUGGACAGCAAUGUAAGGUGAAUAGCUGAGCAUGAUGGCACAAGCUAUAGCCCCAGCUACUUGGGAGGCUGAGGCACAAGGAUUGCUUGAGCAAAUGAGUUGAGUCCAGCAUGGACAACUGUAUUCCUGCAGCCUGCUUGUAUUCCUCUCCUCAAAGUGCUUUUUCCUUCUCUGCCACAUGACUAGUCUGUGAAUUUUCCAAACUUCUACGCUCUGCUUCCCUUUUAAAUAUGUUCCAACUUUAAGUUAUUUCUUUGCUUCCAUAUCUGAUUGUAGGCUGCUAGCAUCAGCCAGGCCACAUCUUGAAUGCUUUGCUGCUUAGAAAUUUCUUCUGCCAGAUACCCUGAUACCCUAAGUCAUCACUCUUAAGUUCAAACUUCCACAGAUUCCUAGGGCCUGGACACAAUGCACCCAAGCUAUUUGCUAAAGCAUGACAUAGAUGUACCUUUAUUCCUGUUCCCAAUAACUUCCUCAUUUCCAUCUGAGACCUCAUCACUCUGGACUUCACCAUAUGUCUAUCAGCAUUUUGGUCACAACCACUUAACUAGUCUCUAAGUUCCAAACUUUCCCUCAUCUUUCUGUCUUCUGAGCCCUCCAGAUUCUUCCAACCUCUGCCUGUUACCCAGUUCCAAAGCUGUUUCUACAUUUUCCAAUAUGUAUAGCAGUGCCCCACUGUCAGUACUAAUCUGUUUUAAUCUGUUUGCAUUACUGUAAAGGAAUAUCUGAGAUUGGGUAAUUCUUGCAAAAGAGAGAUUUAAUUGGCUUACAGUUUCUGCAGGCUGUACACAAAGCAUGGCACCAGCAGCUGCUUCUGAUGAGGGCCUCAGGAAGCUUACAAUCAUGGUAGAAGGCAAAAUGGGAGCGAGCAUAUCACAUGGUGAGAGAGGGAGCAAGAGAGAGGAGGAGGUCCCAGACUCUAAACAACCAAAUUUCACAUGAACUAAGAUCUCACUCAUCACCAAGGUGAUGGUGCCAAGCCAUUCAUGAAGGAUUUGCCCCAUGAUUCUAUACCUCCCACGAGGCCCUACCUCCAGCAUUGGGGGUUACAUUUCAACAUGAGAUUUGGAAGUGACAGCCAUCCAAACCAUAUCAGCAACAUAACAAGACCCCCAACUCUUAAAAAAAAAAGUUGAAUAUAUAUCCAAAAAUAUCUUGAAUUCCAUAUGGAAAGCCUCCCCCCUCAAAUUUGUAGUAAAUUGUAUUAUAAUGAAUACAUUAAUUAAAAAUAUACUUGGCCUGGCACAGUAGCUCAAGCCUGUAAUCCCAGCACUUUGGGAGGCCGAGGCAGGCGGAUCACCUGAGGUCAGGAGUUUUCGAGACCAGCCUGUCCGACAUGGUGAAACUCUGUCUCUACUAAAAAUACAAAAUUAGCCAGCCAUGGUGGCAUAUGCCUGUAAUCCCAGCUACUCACUCAGGAGGCUGAGGCAGGAGAAUCACUUAAACCCAGGAGACGGAGGUUGCAGUGAGUCAAGAUUGCACCGUUGCACUCCAGCCUGGGUGACAGAGUGAGACUCUGUCUGAAAAAAAGUAAAAAUUAAAAAAUAUAUUUGACAAUACCCAGUACCAAUUUAUUGUUUGUUGUUGACAUUAACAUUUUCUUUAAGAGUAUUUCUUCAUCUGUAAAAUGAGGAUAAAAAUUGUAAAAUUGUACCUACUUCCAGCCUCAUAGAAUUGUUUUGAUGAUUACAUCAGAAAGCUUGUAAAAACCUUAGGCCUGUUUCCUGACAUAUACUAAAUGCCCCAUGUGCUAACUGAGGAUGAUCAUUGUAGGAAAAUUUCAUAGACUAUGAGGGAAAGCCAUGCCUAAAAUAAUCUCCAGCUUAUUAAGAAGUGCAUUCCUUUUUGUUUCUUUGUUUUAUCUUAGAUUGAGUCUCACUGUAUUGCCAGUCUGGAGUGCAGUGGCGCAAUCUCAGCUCACUGCAACCUCCACCUCCUGGGUUCAAGCGAUCCUCCUGCCUCAGCCUCCUGAGUAGCUGGGACUACAGGAGCACACCACCACGCCCAGCUAAUUUUUGUGUUUUUAGUAGAGGCGGGGUUUCACCAUGUUGGGCAGGAUGGUCUCAAACUCCUGACCUCAGGUGAUCCACCCGCCUCAACCUCCCAGAGUGCUGGGAUUACAGGCGUGAGCUAUCCGUGCCCAGUCAAUUUUUGUAUUUUUAGUAGAGAUGAGGUUUCACCAUAUUGGUCAGGCUGGUCUUGAACCCCUGACCUCAGGUGAUUCACCCGCCUCAGCCUCCCAAAGUGCUGGGAUUCCAGAUGUGAGCCAGCGCACCCAGCCUGGCCAUCUUUUAUAAAAAGAUGAAGAUGUCAGAAUUCCCUAAUAAGAUUCUGGCUCUGUUACCCAGACUGGAGUGCAAUGCAUGGCAUGAUCUCAGCACACUGCAACCUCCAUCUCCUGGGCUCAAGCCAUCCUCCCACUUCAGUCUCCCAAGUGGCUGGGACUACAGGCACACGCCACCACACCUGGCUAAUUUUUGUAUUUUUUGUAGAGACGAGGUUUCGCCAUGUUACCCAGGCUGGUCUUAAACUCCUGAGUUCAAGUGAUCCACCUGCCUCAGCCUCCCAAAGUGCUGGGAUUACAGGCAUGAGCCACUGUACCCGGCCCCUAAUAAGUUUUAAAUAACCAAUAUUUUAAAAUAUUUUAAUAGUUACAUAGCACUUUAGUUUGCUGAUUUAAUUUAUCCCAAGGGACAAGGAUGUUAAUGAGAAAACUGACUAGAUUUCAGAUCACAGAUUUUAAGAGAACAAGGAUCUCAAAACCAAAUACCCUCUGCUUAAAGUGUUUUUUGUGUUUUUCACUACUGAAAAUGUUUAGAGAUUGACUUACCUAUUGCUGAUACUCAAAACAUCUGAUAUCUUAAUAUUUUUAAAUAACUCACUAAAAGCAUAUGUUGAAAAUGGCAAUGUAUAGUCUGAGACUGGUGAUUAGACUGGACUAAAAGCAUAUGUUGGAAAUGGCAAAUAUAUGAUCUGAGACUGGUGAUUAAUUUACAGUAUUGGCACCUAAAGAGAUACUGAGAUGAAUAACUUAUUAAUUUCCUUCUUAAAAUCAUAAUUUUGGAUCUGUAAAGGACUAUACAAAAAAAAAUUUUAGUAUUAUACCUGCAUUUUAUAAUUGUGGAAAUGGAGGCCAGAAAGAAUAAGAGGCAAGUUAGGGGCAGAUCUUGGGUUUGGAUCAGCUCUUCUGAUGCCUGGUUCUGUGACAUUACAAAGCCUGAAAUUCAGCUCCAACAUCUAUUAAACAUUUGCAGAGUAUCAGCUGGGUGCGGUGGCUCUCAUAAGGCCAGGAGUUCAAGACCAGCCUGGCCAAGAUAGUGAAACCCCAUCUCUACUAAAAAUACAAAAAUUAGCCGGGCAUGGUGGCAAGACACCUGUAAUCCCAGCUACUCUGGAGGCUGAGUCAGAGAAUUGCUUAAACCUGGGAGGCGGAGGUUGCAGUGAUCCCAGAUCGCGCCACUGCGCUCUAGCAUGGGCGACAAAGCGAGACCCCAUCUCAAAAAGAAAAACAAAAUUUUUUUGCAGAGUAUCUACUGUGUGUCAAGUACAUUACCCAAGACUACAAAGAGAAAUACAAUUUAGCUAAUGUCCUCAAGAAGCUAACAGUAUACUAAAAGAGAUAUGUAGGCAUCAAUUAUAGUAAUGACAUAACAUAUUCUAAUAGAGGUAAGUACAUAACACAGUGGGCAUGUCUAGUUGUCUUUGUUUCUGCUGUUAAAACAGAAUAUCACAGACUGGGUGAUGGGUUGAUUGAUUGACUGAUUGAGGCAACUCUGUCACCCAGGCUGGGGUUCAGUGGCAUGAUCACAGUUCACUGCAGCCUCAACCUCCCUGGAUCAAGCAAUCCUCCUGCCUCAGCCUCCUGAACAGCUGGAACUACAGGUGUGAGCCACCAUGCCCCACUAAUUUUUAUUUAUUUAUUUUUUUUUUCUGAGACGGAGUCUCAGUUUGUCGCCCAGGCUGAAGUGCAGUGGCACAAUCUCAGCUCACUGCAACCUCCACCUCCCGGGUUCAGUUUUCCUGCCUCAAUCUACUAGGAUCUAGCUAGGAUUACAGGUGUGCGCCACCAUGCCCAGCUAAUUUUUGUAUUUUUAGUAGAGACGGGGUUUCACCAUGUUGGUCAGGCUGGUCUCAAACUCCUGACCUCAUGAUCUGCCCACCUCGGCCUCCCAAAGUGCUGGGAUUACAGGCGUAAGCCACCGCGCCCAGCUAAUUUUUAAAAAUAUUUUAUAGAGACAGGUCUCACUAUGUUGCCCAGGCUCGUCUUGAACCCCUGGGCCCAGGCGCUCCUCCCACCUUGACCUCCCAAAGUUCUGGAAUUACACAUGUGAGCCAACACACCAGGCCCAGACUGGGUAAUUUAUAAAGAAAUUUACUUCUGCCCACACCGCCCCGCCUCCCCGCGCGAGUGGCUGAGGCGUAGCGCUGCCAUCCCCGCACCCCUGGGAACAUGGCGCUGCGAGUGGUGCGGAGCGUGCGGGCCGUGCUCUGCAGCCUGCACGUGGUCCUGGCACCUGCCGCGCCCUGCCUAUCGAGGCCCUGGCAGCUUGGGAUGGGCGCCGUCUGGUUACUGUAAUCUGCCUGAAGUUGGGACAAAAUUGAACAAACAAGAUGAGUUUGGUGCUUUGGAGAGUGUGAAAGCUGCUAGUGAACUCUAUUCUCCUUUAUCAGGAGAAGUAACCGAAAUUAAUGAAGCUCUUGCAGAAAAUCCAGGACUUGUAAACAAAUCUCGUUAUGAAGAUGGUUGGCUGAUCAAGAUGACACUGAGUAACCCUUCAUAACUAGAUGAACUUAUGAGUGAAGAAGCAUAUGAGAAAUACAUAAAAUCUAUUGAGGAGUGAAAAUGGAACCACUAAAUAAGCUAGUAUGAAAUAACGCAACCCAGCAGAGUUGUCCUAAAUUAGUGGUGGAUAGAAGACUUAGAAUAGCAACUUUUAGCAUUACCCAUGGGAAAAAAAAACUACUGUUAACACUGCUAAUGAAAGAAGAUGCCUUUUAACUUUCUAAUGAUUGUAGAUAAACAUAAUAUGUGUCUUUUUCACAACAUCCUAUGAUUUUUAGACUAGGCUCUAGUAUUCAUGAAAUUAUCCAUGAAAUUAUCCAUGGUAAAAAUUAGUUACAAAAAUUACAUAAUUCAAAGAUAAUGUUGUUAUUCUUAAGCCUUAUAUAAUAUUGUAACUUGUGUAUGUCCAUACCUGGACUUGGGAUGAAAUACUUAAUGAUCUUUCCAUUGGAAAUAACUGGGAGUGAAGAAGUUUUUGUUGCUUGUACAGUGUCAGAUGAAGAACAACACUAUCUUAAUUUUGCAAUACACUGCAUUUGCUGGUGCUGUUUUUAUAUAGUGAAGCAACAGCUGUACAGCAAAAUAAUAAAAUACUCACUUCUUCGUUAAAAAAAAAAAAAAUUUACUUCUUACAAUUCUGGAGGCCAGGAAGACCAUGAUCAGGUGCCAGCAUCUGGGAAGGGCCUUCUUGCUGUCCUCCCAUGGCAGAAGAUGGAAGGGCAAGGGAGAGCUAACAUGCUCCCGCAAACCCUUUUUAUAAUGGCAUCAAUCAAAUAUGAGGCCAGAGUCCUUGUGACCUAAUCAUCUCCCAGAAGGCUCCGCCUCCCAACCCUGUUGCAUUGGGAUUAAGUUUCCAACACAUGAAUUGUGGAGACAACACAUUCAAAACAUAGCAUUCCACACCUUGGGCUCCCCAGAUUCAUGUCCUCACAUGCAAAAUAAAUUCAUUCCAUCCCAAUAGCCCCUAAAAAGUCUUAACUUGUUCCAGCAUCAACUUUAAAGUCAAAGUCCAAAGUCUCAUCUAAAUCAGAUAUGAGUGAGACUCAAGGCAUGAUUCAUCAUGAGACAAAGGAUGUACAUUUGCAAUGUUUGUCAUGUCAGACAAAACAAAAAUAUGUAAAUAUCCAUCAAUAGGGAACUGCUGAAAAAUUUUUUUGUAUAAUCAUAAAAUGAAACAUGCAGAUGUUUAAACCAAUGAGCUAGAUCUCAACGUGCUGAUAUGGAAAGUGCUUCAGAAUGUAUUAAGGACAUAAAUUAAGUGUACAAUAAUGUGUGUGUGUGUAUAUAUGUAUAUGCUUACGUGUGUAUGGAAAGUAUCUCAGCAGAUACAAUAAAAACUUAAUUGUGAUUA